ACACCACAGAGGCGUCUGGCUAACUCAUCUCCAGACCUAAGUUGGGAAAGGGGAGGGGAGCGCGGAAAGCGGAGAAGCCGGAGGAGACGCUCCGGAGUGACCAGCGACGGCUGAACGCAGCCCGCCCUCCCCAAGUCGACGCCGCAACCCGGGGAAAGCAGGUGAGCGCCGGCCACGGACUUGGGGGUCGCAGAAGCAGCCCACGGAGAGCGGAAGGGAGGAGGAUCCGGAUCCCACCACCACCCAAAGAAAAAACCUGGACUCAGCUGCGCGUCCCCUCCCUUCAACCUCCUGCGGGACCCAGAGGUGCCCGGGCCCGCGGGACCCAGGGGUGGCGCGCGCUGCCCCCAACCCCGCACCAUCCCGAGCCAAAUGUGGGAAGAUUAAUGCUGUUGUGGAGGGGAGAGUACUUUGUGACCCCAAGGAGGCGGACAGCAGAGGAGCAUGGAGGACCAUGCGGCAGUAGCAGCCAUGCUGCCCUUUCUGCUGGCCACACUGGGCACCACAGCCCUCAACAACAGCAACCCCAAGGACUACUGCUACAGCGCCCGCAUCCGCAGCACUGUCCUGCAGGGCCUGCCCUUUGGGGGCGUCCCCACCGUGCUGGCUCUCGACUUCAUGUGCUUCCUUGCACUGCUGUUCUUAUUCUCUAUCCUCCGGAAGGUGGCCUGGGACUAUGGGCGGCUGGCCUUGGUGACAGAUGCAGACAGGCUUCGGCGGCAGGAGAGGGACCGAGUGGAACAGGAAUAUGUGGCUUCAGCUAUGCACGGGGACAGCCAUGACCGGUAUGAGCGUCUCACCUCUGUCUCCAGCUCCGUUGACUUUGACCAAAGGGACAAUGGUUUCUGUUCCUGGCUGACAGCCAUCUUCAGGAUAAAGGAUGAUGAGAUCCGGGACAAAUGUGGGGGCGAUGCCGUGCACUACCUGUCCUUUCAGCGGCACAUCAUCGGGCUGCUGGUGGUUGUGGGCGUCCUCUCCGUAGGCAUCGUGCUGCCUGUCAACUUCUCAGGGGACCUGCUGGAGAACAAUGCCUACAGCUUUGGGAGAACCACCAUUGCCAACUUGAAAUCAGGGAACAACCUGCUAUGGCUGCACACCUCCUUCGCCUUCCUGUAUCUGCUGCUCACCGUCUACAGCAUGCGUAGACACACCUCCAAGAUGCGCUACAAGGAGGAUGAUCUGGUGAAGCGGACCCUCUUCAUCAAUGGAAUCUCCAAAUAUGCAGAGUCAGAAAAGAUCAAGAAGCAUUUUGAGGAAGCCUACCCCAACUGCACAGUUCUCGAAGCCCGCCCGUGUUACAACGUGGCUCGCCUAAUGUUCCUCGAUGCAGAGAGGAAGAAGGCCGAGCGGGGAAAGCUGUACUUCACAAACCUCCAGAGCAAGGAGAACGUGCCUACCAUGAUCAACCCCAAGCCCUGUGGCCACCUCUGCUGCUGUGUGGUGCGAGGCUGUGAGCAGGUGGAGGCCAUUGAGUACUACACAAAGCUGGAGCAGAAGCUGAAGGAAGACUACAAGCGGGAGAAGGAGAAGGUGAAUGAGAAGCCUCUUGGCAUGGCCUUUGUCACCUUCCACAAUGAGACUAUCACCGCCAUCAUCCUGAAGGACUUCAACGUGUGUAAAUGCCAGGGCUGCACCUGCCGUGGGGAGCCACGCCCCUCAUCCUGCAGCGAGUCCCUGCACAUCUCCAACUGGACCGUGUCCUAUGCCCCUGACCCUCAGAACAUCUACUGGGAGCACCUCUCCAUCCGAGGCUUCAUCUGGUGGCUGCGCUGCCUGGUCAUCAAUGUCGUCCUCUUCAUCCUCCUCUUCUUCCUCACCACUCCAGCCAUCAUCAUCACCACCAUGGACAAGUUCAACGUCACCAAGCCUGUGGAGUACCUCAACAACCCCAUCAUCACCCAGUUCUUCCCCACCCUGCUGCUGUGGUGCUUCUCGGCCCUCCUUCCCACCAUCGUCUACUACUCAGCCUUCUUUGAAGCCCACUGGACACGCUCUGGGGAGAACAGGACAACCAUGCACAAGUGCUACACUUUCCUCAUCUUCAUGGUGCUGCUCCUACCCUCGCUGGGACUGAGCAGCCUGGACCUCUUCUUCCGCUGGCUCUUUGAUAAGAAAUUCUUGGCUGAGGCAGCUAUUCGGUUUGAGUGUGUGUUCCUGCCCGACAACGGCGCCUUCUUCGUGAACUACGUCAUUGCCUCAGCCUUUAUCGGCAACGCCAUGGACCUGCUGCGCAUCCCAGGCCUGCUCAUGUACAUGAUCCGGCUCUGCCUGGCGCGCUCGGCCGCCGAGAGGCGCAACGUGAAGCGGCAUCAGGCCUACGAGUUCCAGUUUGGCGCAGCCUACGCCUGGAUGAUGUGCGUCUUCACGGUGGUCAUGACCUACAGUAUCACCUGCCCCAUCAUCGUGCCCUUCGGGCUCAUGUACAUGCUGCUGAAGCACCUGGUAGACAGGUACAAUCUCUACUACGCCUACCUGCCGGCCAAGCUGGACAAGAAGAUCCACUCGGGGGCUGUGAACCAGGUGGUGGCCGCGCCCAUCCUCUGCCUCUUCUGGCUGCUCUUCUUUUCCACCAUGCGCACGGGGUUCCUAGCUCCCACGUCUAUGUUCACAUUUGUGGUCCUGGUCAUCACCAUCGUCAUCUGUCUCUGCCACGUCUGCUUUGGACACUUCAAAUACCUCAGUGCCCACAACUACAAGAUUGAGCACACGGAGACAGAUACUGUGGACCCCAGAAGCAAUGGACGGCCCCCCACUGCUGCUGCUGUCCCCAAAUCUGCGAAAUACAUCGCUCAGGUGCUGCAGGACUCAGAGGUGGACGGGGAUGGGGAUGGGGCUCCUGGGAGCUCAGGGGAUGAGCCCCCAUCAUCCUCAUCCCAAGAUGAGGAGUUGCUGAUGCCACCCGACGCCCUCACGGACACAGACUUCCAGUCUUGCGAGGACAGCCUCAUAGAGAAUGAGAUUCACCAGUAAGGGGAGGGAGGGGCCCUGGAGGCCACAUCCUGCCCCACCCCACCCCCACUCCCACGGACACUAAAACGCUAAUAAUUUAUUAGAUCUAAAGCCCCUUCCUCCCCAGCCCCUGCUUUCAUUAAGGUAUUUAAACUUGGGGGUUUCACUGCUCUCCCCCAUGAUGGAGGGAGGGAGCCCCCCAACCUCAGUGAGGAGAGCCCCGAGCCGGCCCCGGGGCAAAGAGGGGUGCAGAGGGAGUUCCCCCAGAUCAGUACCCCCCACCCCUCCCCAGCUAGUAGCAUGACCAGGAGAGGGUUAAUGAGAGCCAAGAGGAGUACCUGGUGCACCUGGUGCCGGUGGCUGGAGACCUGGGGGGCAGGUGGAUCUGGGGCUGUUCCCCCCCCUCCGUUUUUUCCACCCCACAGUUCCUCCUGGGAUCUGGCCCUCCAGGGAAGUGGAGCCUCCAGCCCCUAGGGGAUGCAUGAGGGGGGAGGGGGUGCUGAGUGGGAGGAAGAGUCAGGCUCACAGCUGGGGUGGCCUGGGGGUGGGGGUGGGCAAGGCUGACACUGGAAAAUGGGUUUUUGCACUGUUUUUUUUUUGGUUUUUUUGUUCUUUUUUGUUUUUUUCCUUUAAAAUAAAAACAAAGAAAAGCUCUGA